GCCAUUUCAUCAGGUCAGAGCCAAAGGAAAGCUUGAAAAAUGAAGACAUUAGCAGGACUUGUUCUGGGACUUGUCAUCUUUGAUGCUGCUGUGACUGCCCCAACUCUAGAGUCCAUCAACUAUGACUCAGAAACCUAUGAUGCCACCUUAGAAGACCUGGAUAAUUUGUACAACUAUGAAAACAUACCUGUUGAUAAAGUUGAGAUUGAAAUAGCCACAGUGAUGCCUUCAGGGAACAGAGAGCUCCUCACUCCACCCCCACAGCCUGAGAAGGCCCAGGAAGAGGAAGAGGAGGAGGAAUCUACUCCCAGGCUGAUUGAUGGCUCUUCUCCCCAGGAGCCUGAAUUCACAGGGGUUCUGGGGCCACACACAAAUGAAGACUUUCCAACCUGUCUUUUGUGUACUUGUAUAAGUACCACCGUGUACUGUGAUGACCAUGAACUUGAUGCUAUUCCUCCGCUGCCAAAGAACACCGCUUAUUUCUAUUCCCGCUUUAACAGAAUUAAAAAGAUCAACAAAAAUGACUUUGCAAGCCUAAGUGAUUUAAAAAGGAUUGAUCUGACAUCAAAUUUAAUAUCUGAGAUUGAUGAAGAUGCAUUCCGAAAACUGCCUCAACUUCGAGAGCUUGUCCUGCGUGACAACAAAAUAAGGCAGCUCCCAGAAUUGCCAACCACUUUGACAUUUAUUGAUAUUAGCAACAAUAGACUUGGAAGGAAAGGGAUAAAGCAAGAAGCAUUUAAAGACAUGUAUGAUCUCCAUCAUCUGUACCUCACUGAUAACAACUUGGACCACAUCCCUCUGCCACUCCCAGAAAAUCUACGAGCCCUUCACCUCCAGAAUAACAACAUUCUGGAAAUGCACGAAGAUACGUUCUGCAAUGUUAAAAAUUUGACUUAUAUUCGUAAGGCACUAGAGGACAUUCGAUUGGAUGGAAACCCUAUUAAUCUCAGCAAAACUCCUCAAGCAUACAUGUGUCUACCUCGUCUGCCUGUUGGGAGCCUUGUCUAAUUUCAGAUAAUGGUUAGCAUUACGAUGGCUACUAUAAAUAAACCAUUCUUACUGCUCUCUUCCAAAACAAAACUCAGCAUGAUACUUUGAGAUUGUGUUCUGAGAGAUGAUAUGACUACAUAAAAUACAAUUAAAAAUGUUAUAAUGAAAAUGUAGUAAUUUAAGAAAACACCAGAUGAGUUAGGAAUAAACCUAUAACAUUUACAAAAAGAGCAAAACUAAGUGAUAGAAAAUAUUUCACACAUGUUCUUAUAGAUCAUGUAUCACUUGCAAGUUUUAGGAGUUCAUAUCCUAUAUCAUUUCAAAUUAAGUACAUAAUAAAGUAAAAUUUUGAAAUGAACACUUUAGGUAUUUUUGCCAAGAUUUAGAUGUUUUUAAUUAAACUUUUCUCUUCCUUUUUUUUUCACUAAAGCAUGUUUAUUCCCCUAAUCCAUUAAAGAGCAUGAAAAAAAGAAUAAAUGUAUUUGAAAAUUA